GUAUCGCUCCUCGUAGGCCGGGGCUCGGCGCGCGCACCCGCACUAAAGACGCUUCUUCCCGGCGGGUAGGAAUCCCGCCGGCGAGCCGAACAGUUCCCCGAGCGCAGCCCGCGGACCACCACCCGGCCGCACGGGCCGCUUUUGUCCCCCGCCCGCCGCUUCUGUCCGAGAGGCCGCCCGCGAGGCGCAUCCUGACCGCGAGCGUCGGGUCCCAGAGCCGGGCGCGGCUGGGGCCCGAGGCUAGCAUCUCUCGGGAGCCGCAAGGCGAGAGCUGCAAAGAUGUAAAAGUCAAGAGAAGACUCUAAAAAUAGCAAAGAUGCUUUUGAGCCAGAAUGCCUUCAUCUUCAGAUCACUUAAUUUGGUUCUCAUGGUGUAUAUCAGCCUCGUGUUUGGUAUUUCAUAUGAUUCGCCUGAUUACACAGAUGAAUCUUGCACUUUCAAGAUAUCAUUGCGAAAUUUCCGGUCCAUCUUAUCAUGGGAAUUAAAAAACCACUCCAUUGUACCAACUCACUAUACAUUGCUGUAUACAAUCAUGAGUAAACCAGAAGAUUUGAAGGUGGUUAAGAACUGUGCAAAUACCACAAGAUCAUUUUGUGACCUCACAGAUGAGUGGAGAAGCACACACGAGGCCUAUGUCACCGUCCUAGAAGGAUUCAGCGGGAACACAACGUUGUUCAGUUGCUCACACAAUUUCUGGCUGGCCAUAGACAUGUCUUUUGAACCACCAGAGUUUGAGAUUGUUGGUUUUACCAACCACAUUAAUGUGAUGGUGAAAUUUCCAUCUAUUGUUGAGGAAGAAUUACAGUUUGAUUUAUCUCUCGUCAUUGAAGAACAGUCAGAGGGAAUUGUUAAGAAGCAUAAACCCGAAAUAAAAGGAAACAUGAGUGGAAAUUUCACCUAUAUCAUUGACAAGUUAAUUCCAAACACGAACUACUGUGUAUCUGUUUAUUUAGAGCACAGUGAUGAGCAAGCAGUAAUAAAGUCUCCCUUAAAAUGCACCCUCCUUCCACCUGGCCAGGAAUCAGCAUUGGGAAUGGUACCACCUCCCGAAAAUGUCAGAAUGAAUUCUGUUAAUUUCAAGAACAUUCUACAGUGGGAGUCACCUGCUUUUGCCAAAGGGAACCUGACUUUCACAGCUCAGUACCUAAGUUAUAGGAUAUUCCAAGAUAAAUGCAUGAAUACUACCUUGACGGAAUGUGAUUUCUCAAGUCUUUCCAAGUAUGGUGACCACACCUUGAGAGUCAGGGCUGAAUUUGCAGAUGAGCAUUCAGACUGGGUAAACAUCACCUUCUGUCCUGUGGAUGACACCAUUAUUGGACCCCCUGGAAUGCAAGUAGAAGUACUUGCUGAUUCUUUACAUAUGCGUUUCUUAGCCCCUAAAAUUGAGAAUGAAUACGAAACUUGGACUAUGAAGAAUGUGUAUAACUCAUGGACUUAUAAUGUGCAAUACUGGAAAAACGGUACUGAUGAAAAGUUUCAAAUUACUCCCCAGUAUGACUUUGAGGUCCUCAGAAACCUGGAGCCAUGGACAACUUAUUGUGUUCAAGUUCGAGGGUUUCUUCCUGAUCGGAACAAAGCUGGGGAAUGGAGUGAGCCUGUCUGUGAGCAAACAACCCAUGACGAAACGGUCCCCUCCUGGAUGGUGGCCGUCAUCCUCAUGGCCUCGGUCUUCAUGGUCUGCCUGGCACUCCUCGGCUGCUUCGCCUUGCUGUGGUGCGUUUACAAGAAGACAAAGUACGCCUUCUCCCCUAGGAAUUCUCUUCCACAGCACCUGAAAGAGUUUUUGGGCCAUCCUCAUCAUAACACACUUCUGUUUUUCUCCUUUCCAUUGUCGGAUGAGAAUGAUGUUUUUGACAAGCUAAGUGUCAUUGCAGAAGACUCUGAGAGCGGCAAGCAGAAUCCUGGUGACAGCUGCAGCCUCGGGACCCCGCCUGGGCAGGGGCCCCAAAGCUAGGCUCUGAGAAGGAAACACACUCGGCUGGGCACAGUGACGUACUCCAUCUCACAUCUGCCUCAGUGAGGGAUCAGGGCAGCAAACAAGGGCCAAGACCAUCUGAGCCAGCCCCACAUCUAGAACUCCCAGACCCUGGACUUAGCCACCAGAGAGCUACAUUUUAAAGGCUGUCUUGGCAAAAAUACUCCAUUUGGGAACUCACUGCCUUAUAAAGGCUUUCAUGAUGUUUUCAGAAGUUGGCCACUGAGAGUGUAAUUUUCAGCCUUUUAUAUCACUAAAAUAAGAUCAUGUUUUAAUUGUGAGAAACAGGGCCGAGCACAGUGGCUCACGCCUGUAAUACCAGCACCUUAGAGGUCGAGGCAGGCGGAUCACUUGAGGUCAGGAGUUCAAGACCAGCCUGGCCAAUAUGGUGAAACCCAGUCUCUACUAAAAAUACAAAAAUUAGCUAGGCAUGAUGGCGCAUGCCUAUAAUCCCAGCUACUCGAGUGCCUGAGGCAGGAGAAUUGCAUGAACCCGGGAGGAGGAGGAGGAGGUUGCAGUGAGCCGAGAUAGCGGCACUGCACUCCAGCCUGGGUGACAAAGUGAGACUCCAUCUCAAAAAAAAAAAAAAAAAAAAUUGUGAGAAACAGAAAUACUUAAAAUGAGGAAUAAGAAUGGAGAUGUUACAUCUGGUAGAUGUAACAUUCUACCAGAUUAUGGAUGGACUGAUCUGAAAAUCGACCUCAACUCAAGGGUGGUCAGCUCAAUGCUACACAGAGCACGGACUUUUGGAUUCUUUGCAGUACUUUGAAUUUAUUUUUCUACCUAUAUAUGUUUUAUAUGCUGCUGGUGCUCCAUUAAAGUUUUACUCUGUGUUGCACUAUA